AAAGCCAUCGCUCCUUCUUUCUGGCCGGAUGUGUGCUGAGACCCAGAGUCACCCAGGGGUCUCCGUCACGUGCCAGGAGUAGGCAGAAGUGGGCUGUGACAGAUCAGGAAACAGAGCUCAGUGCAGCCCACUAAAUUGCUCAGGGCCCUACAGCUAACAAGCGGCAGAGGCAGGAUCUGCACUCAGGAGCUGCUUGGAGAUGCUGCUGUGGCCACUGCUGCUGCUGCUGCUGCUGCUGCCAACAUUGGCCCUGCUCAGGCAGCAGCGGUCCCAGGAUGCCAGGCUGUCCUGGCUUGCUGGCCUCCAGCACCGAGUGGCAUGGGGGGCCCUGGUCUGGGCAGCCACCUGGCAGCGGCGGAGGCUGGAGCAGAGCACGCUCCAUGUGCACCAGAGCCAGCAGCAGGCCCUGAGGUGGUGUCUACAGGGAGCCCAGCGCCCCCACUGUUCCCUCAGAAGGAGCACAGACAUAAGCACCUUCCGGAAUCAUCUCCCUCUGACCAAGGCCAGCCAGACCCAGCAGGAAGACAGUGGAGAGCAGCCACUGCCCCCGACCUCAAACCAGGACCUUGGGGAGGCCUCUCUGCAGGCCACCUUGCUGGGUCUGGCAGCCCUAAACAAGGCCUACCCAGAAGUGCUGGCUCAGGGACGCACUGCCCGUGUGACGCUUACAUCCCCUUGGCCCCGACCCCUGCCUUGGCCUGGGAAUACCCUGGGCCAGGUGGGCACCCCUGGAACCAAGGACCCUAGGGCCCUGCUGCUGGACGCACUGAGGUCCCCAGGGCUGAGGGCACUGGAGGCUGGGACGGCUGUCGAACUUCUGGAUGUUUUCUUGGGCCUGGAGACUGAUGGUGAAGAGCUAGCUGGGGCGAUAGCUGCCGGGAACCCUGGAGCGCCUCUCCGUGAACGGGCAGCUGAGCUCCGGGAGGCCCUAGAGCAGGGGCCACGGGGACUGGCCCUUCGGCUCUGGCCAAAGCUGCAGGUGGUGGUGACUCUGGAUGCAGGAGGCCAGGCCGAGGCUGUGGCUGCCCUCGGGGCCUUGUGGUGCCAAGGACUAGCCUUCUUCUCUCCUGCUUAUGCUGCCUCGGGAGGGGUGCUGGGCCUAAACCUACAGCCAGAGCAGCCCCAUGGGCUCUACCUUCUGCCCCCUGGGGCCCCCUUUAUCGAGCUGCUCCCAGUCAAGGAAGGCACCCAGGAGGAAGCUGCCUCCACCCUCCUUUUGGCCGAGGCCCAGCAGGGCAAGGAGUAUGAGCUGGUGCUGACGGACCGCGCCAGCCUCACCAGGUGCCGCCUGGGUGAUGUGGUGCGAGUGGUUGGUGCCUACAAUCAGUGUCCAGUCGUCAGGUUCAUCUGCAGGCUGGACCAGACCCUGAGUGUGCGAGGGGAAGAUAUUGGUGAAGACCUGUUCUCUGAGGCCCUGGGCCGGGCAGUGGGGCAGUGGGCGGGGGCCAAGCUGCUGGACCAUGGCUGUGUGGAGAGCAGCAUUCUGGAGUGGGGAAGAACAGAUAGGGCAGAGGACACUAGACUUGGCAGCUGCCCAUUCACCGGAAGUAUGUGUGCACAUGGGGUCUAUUCACAGAUUCCUCUGCGGGCUCUGCUCCCCACUACGAGGUGUUUGUGGCGCUGAGGGGGCUGAGGAAUCUGUCAGAGGAAAAUCGAGACAAGCUGGACCACUGCCUUCAGGAAGCCUCUCCCCGCUACAAGUCCCUGCGGUUCUGGGGCAGCGUGGGCCCUGCCAGAGUCCACCUGGUGGGGCAGGGAGCCUUCCGAGCACUCCGGGCAGCCCUCGCUGCCUGCCCCUCCUCCCCCUUCCCCCCUGCGAUGCCCCGGGUCCUUCGGCACAGGCACCUGGCCCAGUGUCUGCAGGAGAGGGUGGUGUCCUGAGUCAAGUCCUGCCCCACCGCCCAGCUCCCCCCAGAGGCCACCUCGCCCCUCCCUCUGGGACCUCUCCGGAUGGGGAGUCCUUGGCCAGGGUCUCUGACUCUGUGUCACCUGACAUUUGCCCAUGAGAGCCGCUGGGCCUUAGAGAGGCCUUGGCCCAGCUGACCGGUUCUGAAGUAUGGGCCUCCGGGGUUAGCAGAUGCCAGCAGUGCCUGCCCGUGUCCCCAUGUCCCGGCAUGAAGGACACUGCUAGAGAGUUACCAUGCACACCGAUGGUUUCCUGUAUCACAGCCCAAAGAGGUUCUCUGGUGGCCACAGCUGUGUGCUCAGUCAGUGCACUGGGCAAGCUAGAAGUGUUGGGGGGUUAAUGUCCCCAGGAGCAGCAACCCUGAGUCAAUAAGGAGCAGGACCUCAGCUUCAUUGUCCUUGAGCAGGACAAUUCUGAAGUGUAUUCUACAUAAACUCUCAGAGGAUGCCCAGCAGGAUGGAGUCCCAGUUGCCCGCAGCAGUAACCCACUCAUUCAUGUACUUCCUGCGGGGGCUCUCCCUUCCCUCUCUUCCCCACUCCCCCGCCUUGGGCUUCCUGGGAUGGCUCCCAAAUAAACCUCUUGCACCCAGA